AUAUGUAAGCUGACAAGAGGCAGACAAACACGUUCUGAAGUUUUGUGCAUGCUGCGUUUUCUCUCCUUGCUGCAACAAGAAAAGCCUUUGUUUUCCAACCUGGCAACCUUUGAAGAAGUGACUCAGACAUCUUCAUGGCCUCUAAAGAUGCCCAGAACCAAAGAAGAGGUCUGCCUGGUUUUCUUCCUGGAGCUCCAGACCCAGACCAAAGCCUUCCUGCCUCUUCCAAUCCAGGGAACCAAGCAUGGCAGCUGAGUCUCCCUCUGCCAAGCAGUUUCCUGCCAACAGUCAGUCUCCCUCCUGGUCUAGAAUAUUUAAGCCAGUUAGACCUGAUAAUUAUACACCAGCAGGUGGAGCUGCUUGGAAUGAUACUUGGUACUGAGACCUCCAACAAAUAUGAGAUUAAAAACAGCUUGGGACAAAGAAUUUACUUUGCAGUGGAGGAAAGCAUCUGCUUCAAUCGUACUUUCUGUUCCACUCUGCGAUCUUGCACCCUGAGGAUCACAGAUAACUCAGGUCGAGAGGUCAUUACAGUGAACAGGCCCUUGAGAUGUAACAGCUGCUGGUGCCCUUGCUACCUACAAGAGUUAGAAAUCCAAGCCCCUCCUGGUACUAUAGUUGGUUACGUUACGCAGAAGUGGGACCCCUUUCUGCCUAAAUUCACAAUCCAAAAUGCAAACAAAGAAGAUAUUUUGAAAAUUGUUGGUCCUUGUGUGACAUGUGGCUGUUUUGGCGAUGUGGAUUUUGAGGUGAAAACCAUUAAUGAAAAGCUUACAAUUGGGAAGAUUUCAAAGUACUGGUCAGGAUUUGUAAAUGAUGUCUUCACAAAUGCUGACAAUUUCGGAAUUCAUGUUCCUGCAGAUCUAGAUGUAACAGUCAAAGCAGCAAUGAUCGGUGCCUGUUUUCUCUUUGUAAGUAUGGGCUUUGAGAGCAUGAGUGAUUUGUUAUUCUCCCUCUUGCUUGUUAAUUACAAUAUAGCCUAUCCCAUUUACACAGUUUUUACCCCCAAAGAGUAUAUUUUAUUCAUAGAAGGAUAGCUUAGGACCAAUGUUCUUCAAAAAUUAGAAUUUAGAACCCUGCAUUUCUGUUAGGCAGCCCCUCUUCAGUGAUCUCAUAUCCCCUUUCUCAAAGAUUGAAGUGUUAUCACAUCCUAUUCAUCAUUUCUUUAAAACCUAGUUUCCCCUUGCUUUU